GCGCUGAGACGCGCCCGGCUGCUGCCGCCGCCCUCCUUUCCCCUCUUCCCUGGUUUCCCUUCUCCUCUAGACCUGUUCGCUCUCCGCCCCUCCUUGCCUCCCCAACACCCCCUCAGGUCCCGUUGCCUCCUGGUCCUUUCAGGGAUUCCUGGUCCUUCCUUCCCACACUAGCCUCCCUGGGGUAUCGCUGAGGCAGCCUGGCCUGCACCCAGGUUCCCCUCACCCCUGCCACAUUUCUCUCUUCUCCCUCACGCCAACUUUCCUUUUCGCCCUUCUCUCUCUUUCUCACAUCCUAGAGACGGUCUUUAAUACGCAUUAACCCUGUGCUGCCACAUCUGGCUCCUGCCCUCAUUGCCUCCAAUCCGGACUCUUCCUCUCACAUCACCCCCACCACCCCCAACUUGGGCUCACAACUUCUCUUCACUUUUUCCAUUUCCCCAGUUCUCUGCCUUCCGUCUUUCCCUCUGUCCUCAUCCUUAGCCCCUCUGCCCUGCUUUGUGUCCCACCUCUCCCCCUCCACUUCCUCUCCUCCCACCCUCAGUCUCACCCCCGGGCUGUCUCACUCUCUGGAGCCUCUCCUUCCUGUUCUCUGUCCCCAGUGCUCCCUACCCUCACCUCAAGACGACCAUGGCCACCAUCCCAGACUGGAAGCUACAGCUGCUAGCCCGGCGCCGGCAGGAGGAGGCGUCCGUUCGAGGCCGAGAGAAAGCAGAACGGGAGCGCCUGUCCCAGAUGCCAGCCUGGAAACGAGGGCUCCUGGAGCGCCGCCGGGCCAAGCUUGGGCUGUCCCCUGGGGAGCCUAGCCCUGUGCUAGGGACUGUAGAGGCUGGACCUCCAGACCCGGAUGAGUCUGCGGUCCUUCUGGAGGCCAUCGGGCCAGUGCACCAGAACCGAUUCAUCCGGCAGGAGCGGCAGCAGCAGCAGCAGCAACAACAACGGAGUGAAGAGCUGCUAGCAGAGAGAAAGCCUGGGCCUCUGGAGGCCCGGGAGCGGAGACCCAGCCCUGGGGAGAUGCGGGAUCAGAGCCCCAAGGGAAGAGAGUCAAGAGAAGAGAGACUAAGUCCGAGGGAGACCAGAGAGAGGAGGCUGGGGAUAGGGGGAGCCCAAGAGUUGAGCCUGAGGCCUCUGGAGGCUCGGGACUGGAGGCAAAGCCCAGGAGAGGUGGGAGACAGGAGCUCCCGACUGUCAGAGGCAUGGAAAUGGAGGCUGAGUCCUGGAGAAACUCCAGAGCGGAGUCUGAGACUAGCAGAGUCUCGAGAGCAAAGCCCCAGGAGAAAAGAGGUGGAAAGUAGACUGAGCCCAGGGGAAUCUGCCUACCAGAAGUUGGGCCUGACAGAGGCCCAUAAAUGGAGACCUGACUCCAGAGAGUCUCAGGAACAGAGUUUGGUACAACUGGAGGCAACAGAGUGGAGGCUGAGGUCAGGAGAAGAAAGACAAGACUACUCGGAAGAAUGUGGGAGAAAAGAAGAGUGGCCAGUUCCAGGGGUAGCUCCAAAAGAGACUGCAGAGCUGUCCGAGACCCUGACAAGGGAGGCCCAAGGCAACAGUUCCGCAGGAGUGGAGGCAGCAGAGCAGAGGCCUGUGGAAGAUGGCGAGAGGGGCAUGAAGCCAACAGAAGGGUGGAAAUGGACCCUGAACUCCGGGAAGGCUCGAGAAUGGACACCCAGGGACAUAGAGGCUCAAACUCAGAAACCAGAACCUCCAGAGUCAGCAGAGAAGCUUCUGGAAUCUCCCGGUGUGGAGGCUGGAGAAGGGGAGGCUGAGAAGGAGGAGGCGGGGGCUCAGGGCAGGCCUCUGAGAGCCCUGCAGAACUGCUGCUCUGUGCCCUCCCCCCUCCCACCAGAGGACGCUGGGACUGGAGGCCUGAGACAGCAGGAAGAGGAAGCAGUGGAGCUCCAGCCCCCACCACCAGCCCCUCUGUCUCCCCCACCCCCAGCCCCAACUGCCCCCCAACCUCCUGGGGAUCCCCUCAUGAGCCGCCUGUUCUAUGGGGUGAAGGCAGGGCCAGGGGUGGGGGCCCCCCGCCGCAGUGGACACACCUUCACCGUCAACCCCCGGCGGUCUGUGCCCCCUGCGACCCCAGCCACCCCAACCUCUCCAGCCACAGUUGAUGCUGCAGUCCCGGGGGCUGGGAAGAAGCGGUACCCAACUGCCGAGGAGAUCUUGGUUCUGGGGGGCUACCUCCGUCUCAGCCGCAGCUGCCUUGCCAAGGGGUCCCCCGAAAGACACCACAAACAGCUUAAGAUCUCCUUCAGCGAGACAGCCCUGGAGACCACGUACCAAUACCCCUCCGAGAGUUCGGUACUGGAGGAGCUGGGCCCGGAGCCUGAGGUCCCCAGUGCCCCCAACCCUCCAGCAGCCCAACCCGACGACGAAGAGGAUGAGGAAGAGCUGCUGCUCCUGCAGCCAGAGCUCCAGGGCGGGCUGCGCACCAAGGCCCUGAUUGUGGAUGAGUCCUGCCGGCGGUGACCAUCUUCCAACAUAGGGAUAUACCUCCCUCCUUCUUAUAACUGAAGAUCCUGGAGCCCGGAAGAUUCAGGGCAGACAGACCCUGAUAAUGAGCCUGGCAGGGAAGGGCAACCAACAUCUUGUAACUUGCUUUCCCCACCCUGUUUCUGGGGGCAGAGCCAAUUGCCCAAUUUCUACCCUAAUCCAAAGUCCCUGGUGUGGGUGGGGUUAAACGUGCUGGUGCAUCCUAGGUCAUCCAAGAGUGAGCGCCAAGUCCUGAGAAGGGGCACAGAACUCCCUGGAGGGUGGAGAUGGAGCACCUGCCCCCCAUGGCAGGGUACACUCUCCCCACAGCCUUCCUCCCCACCAUCCCGUGGGGACUCUCGGGAUUUAAGCACUCGUCUCUCUGGGAGGCCCAGACCCCACUCCAUUUAUAGGCACAUCUCCUUCAUUUCCUAGGUCACUGCCCCUUUGUUUACAGCUCCUGCCUCCUCCCUUGACCACAGCCUGGUUUACAAAUUCCAUCAGCUCCCAGCCCCACCUGCCAAAGUCCCAGGUUUACAAGCCACGCUUACUUGCUGUGUCUGCGUGGAAUUCUCUCCUCUGUCCCCUCCAGUCUCCUCAUUGGAGUGACCUGAAGGUGUGGCUUCCUCCACUUUUUCUCAGUAUUACUUUGCCUUAGUUUUCCCCAAGAGGGAAGGCUGGAACUCUUAACUCUGUACCCCUUGAUAGUUAUUUAAUUCUGUUUCUCCUAGUGGUUCACAAUUGAACUGAAUUGAGAUGGUGUCGGGUGGCUAAGGAGACACCUCACCUCUCCUUCCCCAUUGUGCCGCCUUUAUCAAUUGCCUGUUUUGUUUUGUUUGUUUUUUAACUUUCCAUAAUAAAAUGGAGUUCUCUUCAA